ACACGGGCACACACGCGCGCACGGGAUCCUGCUCCGCUCCGCGGCUCCCCCGCCCCGGAGAGCUCCGCGAUCAGCACCCGGGACAGCGCCACCGCCCACGUGCAGGGGGUGGGGUCCGGGCGGGGCUGGCGCCUCGGCGUCUCCCGGGAGUGUCCCGUCCAGCCGCCGAGCAGGUAGGAGCUGCUGGGACCCCCGCCCUCAGCCCAUCCGCAUCCGCAUCCCUAGAGGAAAGGGGUGUGCGAGUGGGGGCUGGGGCACUGGGGAGACAACCAGAGGGAGGGCAGCAGCCUGAAGCGGAGAGACAGGGAUCUGGGGACGCGAGACAGAAAAGACUCCAGGACCCCGCCACCAUGUUCCCGGAGCCCCCAACCCCGGGGCCUCCAUCGCCCGACACGCCUCCCGACUCCAGUCGCAUCAGCCACGGCCCAGUGCCCCCCUGGGCCCUGGCCACCAUCGUGCUGGUCUCAGGCCUCCUCAUCUUCAGCUGCUGUUUCUGUCUCUACCGGAAGAGCUGUCGGAGGCGGACAGGCAAGAAGAGCCAGGCCCAAGCCCAGGUCCACCUUCAGGAAGUGAAGGGGCUGGGCCAGAGUUACAUAGACAAGGUGCAGCCAGAAGUAGAGGAGCUGGAGCCAGCACCAUCCGGGCCAGGGCAGCAGGUGGCAGACAAGCAUGAGCUAGGACGACUGCAGUACUCCCUGGAUUAUGACUUCCAGAGUGGCCAGCUGCUGGUGGGCAUUCUGCAAGCAAUGGGAUUGGCAGCCUUGGAUCUUGGUGGCUCCUCGGACCCCUAUGUGCGGGUCUACCUGCUGCCGGACAAACGGAGGCGGUACGAGACCAAGGUGCAUCGGCAGACGCUGAACCCUCACUUUGGGGAGACCUUCGCCUUCAAGGUCCCCUACGUGGAGCUGGGGGGCAGGGUGCUGGUCAUGGCGGUGUACGACUUCGACCGCUUCUCUCGCAAUGACGCCAUCGGGGAGGUGCGGGUCCCUAUGAGCUCCGUGGACCUGGGGCGGCCAGUGCAGGCCUGGCGGGAGCUGCAGGCGGCUCCGCGGGAGGAGCAGGAGAAGCUUGGGGACAUCUGCUUCUCCCUCCGCUAUGUCCCCACGGCCGGGAAGCUCACCGUCAUCGUCCUGGAGGCUAAAAACCUGAAGAAGAUGGACGUAGGAGGACUGUCAGAUCCAUACGUCAAGGUCCACCUGCUGCAGGGCGGCAAAAAGGUGCGGAAGAAGAAAACCACCAUCAAGAAGAACACUCUGAACCCCUAUUACAACGAAGCUUUCAGCUUCGAGGUGCCCUGUGACCAAGUCCAGAAGGUGCAGGUGGAGCUGACCGUGCUGGACUACGACAAGCUGGGCAAGAACGAGGCCAUCGGGAGGGUGGCCGUGGGGGCGGCCGCCGGCGGGGCUGGCCUGCGGCACUGGGCGGACAUGCUGGCCAACCCGCGGCGGCCCAUUGCCCAGUGGCACUCGCUGCGGCCCCCGGACCGAGUGAGGCUGCUGCCUGCGCCCUGACUCCCACCCCAAGCCCCCGGCCAAGCCUGGACUCUAGCCCCUGACCCCAGACUCCCGAGACCGGCCAAAGCCAAGCCAGCCCCACCCUUAAGCUUCCUCUGACGGUUACCCUCCCCCCACCUUCCACCCCAACCAUCUGAACCAUUCCUGUCUUCUCACCCCCAACGAUGCCAAUCACGACAACUUUCCAGCACACUCCCCCGACCCUCGCGGACACACCCAGAUGCCCCAGGGACCCCGGGAAGGGAAGGCAGCCUGGUUUCUCCUGCCCCCGGGUCCUGCCCCCUGCUUUGACAAUCAGCCAUCCUCGUCUGCUCUCCUCUCUCUUCCAACACAGCCCAUCCCUGCACUGCUCCUGGGGCCAAAUAAAUAUUCAGCAGCUCCGGUGGCCUGGGCCCAUGCUCCUUGAUGGGGGUGGGCAAGGGCUGGGACCCAAGAGGAAACCUCGUUUCCAGGAAUGGGCGCUCGCAGGGCGGUGUGAGUGCUGUUCGUCCUGAAAGCCUCUGAGAGACUGGCCUGACCCCAUGGACUCCCUCACACUCUCACCCGUUCAUUCCUCACUCACCACUCUGAGCCUGGGUUUCCUCCUCUGGAGAAUGUUGGGAUAAUAAUAAUUCCUGCCACACGCUGGCUGUGAGGAGUCCGCGAGAACUCCCUUGCUUGUCCAUGAAUUUAUCCACUCGCUUGCUCACCCAUGACUCACAUCGAUUUUCAUACCCAUUUCUGCAUCCCUCCCUCCCUCUCUUUUUUUUCUUCCUUCCAUUCCAUAUUCCCUGAGGUCUUCUGUUGAGUGCUGGGGCCCCAGAAUAUCCAAACACAGACCUGACCCCCCAAGCGACUUACUGCCAUCAAAACAAAGGAGAGGCGCGGAGCCAGGGAAUACAAUCUCCAGAGCCUGCGAGAGAGGUUGGAGUUCAGCAAGGAAAGCCAAUGAUUUCAACUUCACCUCUUUCUUUUUUCUUUUCUUUUUUCCUUUUUGUUUUCUUUCUGUCUUUCCUUUUCUUUCUUUUUCUCUUGUUUUUUUUUUGUUUGUUUGUUUUUUUGUUUUUGUUUUUGUUUUUUUGAGAUGAAGUCUCACUUUGUCGCCCAGGCUGGAGUGCAGUGGCACGAUUUCGGCUCACUGCAAGCUCCUCCUCCCGGGUUCACGCCAUUCUCCUGCCUCAGCCUCCCGAGCAGCUGGGACUACAGGCGCCCGCCACCACACCCGGCUAAUUUUUUUGUAUUUUUAGUAGAGACGGCAUUUCACCGUGUUAGCCAGGAUGAUCUCGAUCUCCUGACCUCGUGAUCCGCCCGCCUCGGCCUCCCAAUGUGCUAGGAUUACAGGCGUGAGCCACCGCGCCCGGCCCUUCUUCUUUUCUUUUCUUUUCUAUUUCUUUUCUUCUCUUCUUCUUUUUUUUAAUUUUGAGACGGAGUUUCGCUGUUGUUGCCCAGAAUGGAGGGCAAUGGUGCAAUCUCGGCUCACCGCAACCCCUGCCUCCCGGGUUCAAGCGAUUCUUCUGCCUCAGCCUCUUCUUUCUUCUUUUUUUGACAGGGUUUCUCUGUGUACCCUGGCUGGAGUGCGGUGGGGCAAUCAUAGCUCACUGCAGCCUCAACCUCCUGGGCUCAGGGGAUCCUCCUGCCUCAGACUCCUGAGUAGCUGGGACCACAGGCACAUGCAACCAUGCCUAGCUAAUUUUUUCUUUUCUUUUCUUUUCUUUUUUAGAGAUGGGGUCUUGCUAUGUUGCACAGGCUGGUUUCAAACUCCUGCAAUCCUCCUGUGUGAGUAGCUGGGACUGUAGACAUGAGCCGCCGCAUCUGACCUCAUUGUUCUUUCAACGAAUGCUGCCUCCUACUCUGUUUCUAGCAAAGAUGAUAGUUCCAUUGGCUUCUACCUUAUCUCAUCCCAUACAGAAUUUUGGGUGGUGAACAAAGACCUAUAAGAUUUGGCCAGAGAACUCUCUGAGCAGCAGAUUAAGUGGAGAAUGAGGCAAAAAUUACCCCCACGUACCAAAAAAGGAGGCAGCAAACAAACUUACUUGCUCCUAAGCUUCCUGGUAGCCAAUCGGGAAAGUGAAAAUAGAACAGCUACACAGAUUAUAAUAUCCAUGAGAUUUUUAAUUUUUCUCCAAAGGAAUUCAGUAACUUUUCAUGUGUGUGAGUGUGUGUGUGUGUGUGUGUGUGUGUGUGUGUGUGUGUGUGGCUGUAGAGCAUGUCUUUAUGAAGACAGCCCUUUAUGUUACUACUAUUACUGCCAAUAAUAAUCCUCACAGCAAACUCAUGAAAUAAACAUGAUCAUUAUUCCCAGUUGA